CUGCCCGCCGCUGGGUCCGACCGCGCUCGCCUUCCUUGCAGCCGCGCCUCGGCCCCAUGGACGCCCUGUGCGGUUCCGGGGAGCUCGGCUCCAAGUUCUGGGACUCCAACCUGUCUGUGCACACAGAAAACCCGGACCUCACUCCCUGCUUCCAGAACUCCCUGCUGGCCUGGGUGCCCUGCAUCUACCUGUGGGUCGCCCUGCCCUGCUACUUGCUCUACCUGCGGCACCAUUGUCGUGGCUACAUCAUCCUCUCCCACCUGUCCAAGCUCAAGAUGGUCCUGGGUGUCCUGCUGUGGUGCGUCUCCUGGGCGGACCUUUUUUACUCCUUCCAUGGCCUGGUCCAUGGCCGGGCCCCUGCCCCUGUUUUCUUUGUCACCCCCUUGGUGGUGGGGGUCACCAUGCUGCUGGCCACCCUGCUGAUACAGUAUGAGCGGCUGCAGGGCGUACAGUCUUCGGGGGUCCUCAUUAUCUUCUGGUUCCUGUGUGUGGUCUGCGCCAUCGUCCCAUUCCGCUCCAAGAUCCUUUUAGCCAAGGCAGAGGGUGAGAUCUCAGACCCCUUCCGCUUCACCACCUUCUACAUCCACUUUGCCCUGGUACUCUCUGCCCUCAUCUUGGCCUGCUUCAGGGAGAAACCUCCAUUUUUCUCCGCAAAGAAUGUCGACCCUAACCCCUACCCUGAGACCAGCGCUGGCUUUCUCUCCCGCCUGUUUUUCUGGUGGUUCACAAAGAUGGCCAUCUAUGGCUACCGGCAUCCCCUGGAGGAGAAGGACCUCUGGUCCCUAAAGGAAGAGGACAGAUCCCAGAUGGUGGUGCAGCAGCUGCUGGAGGCAUGGAGGAAGCAGGAAAAGCAGACGGCACGACACAAGGCUUCAGCAGCACCUGGGAAAAAUGCCUCCGGCGAGGACGAGGUGCUGCUGGGUGCCCGGCCCAGGCCCCGGAAGCCCUCCUUCCUGAAGGCCCUGCUGGCCACCUUCGGCUCCAGCUUCCUCAUCAGUGCCUGCUUCAAGCUUAUCCAGGACCUGCUCUCCUUCAUCAAUCCACAGCUGCUCAGCAUCCUGAUCAGGUUUAUCUCCAACCCCAUGGCCCCCUCCUGGUGGGGCUUCCUGGUGGCUGGGCUGAUGUUCCUGUGCUCCAUGAUGCAGUCGCUGAUCUUACAACACUAUUACCACUACAUCUUUGUGACUGGGGUGAAGUUUCGUACUGGGAUCAUGGGUGUCAUCUACAGGAAGGCUCUGGUUAUCACCAACUCAGUCAAACGUGCGUCCACUGUGGGGGAAAUUGUCAACCUCAUGUCAGUGGAUGCCCAGCGCUUCAUGGACCUUGCCCCCUUCCUCAAUCUGCUGUGGUCAGCACCCCUGCAGAUCAUCCUGGCGAUCUACUUCCUCUGGCAGAACCUAGGUCCCUCUGUCCUGGCUGGAGUCGCUUUCAUGGUCUUGCUGAUUCCACUCAACGGAGCUGUGGCCGUGAAGAUGCGCGCCUUCCAGGUAAAGCAAAUGAAAUUGAAGGACUCGCGCAUCAAGCUGAUGAGUGAGAUCCUGAACGGCAUCAAGGUGCUGAAGCUGUACGCCUGGGAGCCCAGCUUCCUGAAGCAGGUGGAGGGCAUCAGGCAGGGUGAGCUCCAGCUGCUGCGCACGGCGGCCUACCUCCACACCACAACCACCUUCACCUGGAUGUGCAGCCCCUUCCUGGUGACCCUGAUCACCCUCUGGGUGUACGUGUACGUGGACCCAAACAAUGUGCUGGACGCCGAGAAGGCCUUUGUGUCUGUGUCCUUGUUUAAUAUCUUAAGACUUCCCCUCAACAUGCUGCCCCAGUUAAUCAGCAACCUGACUCAGGCCAGUGUGUCUCUGAAACGGAUCCAGCAAUUCCUGAGCCAAGAGGAACUUGACCCCCAGAGUGUGGAAAGAAAGACCAUCUCCCCAGGCUAUGCCAUCACCAUACACAGUGGCACCUUCACCUGGGCCCAGGACCUGCCCCCCACUCUGCACAGCCUAGACAUCCAGGUCCCGAAAGGGGCACUGGUGGCCGUGGUGGGGCCUGUGGGCUGUGGGAAGUCCUCCCUGGUGUCUGCCCUGCUGGGAGAGAUGGAGAAGCUAGAAGGCAAAGUGCACAUGAAGGGCUCCGUGGCCUAUGUGCCCCAGCAGGCAUGGAUCCAGAACUGCACUCUUCAGGAAAACGUGCUUUUCGGCAAAGCCCUGAACCCCAAGCGCUACCAGCAGACUCUGGAGGCCUGUGCCUUGCUAGCUGACCUGGAGAUGCUGCCUGGUGGGGAUCAGACAGAGAUUGGAGAGAAGGGCAUUAACCUGUCUGGGGGCCAGCGGCAGCGGGUCAGUCUGGCUCGAGCUGUUUACAGUGAUGCCGAUAUUUUCUUGCUGGAUGACCCACUGUCCGCGGUGGACUCUCAUGUGGCCAAGCACAUCUUUGACCACGUCAUCGGGCCAGAAGGCGUGCUGGCAGGCAAGACGCGAGUGCUGGUGACGCACGGCAUUAGCUUCCUGCCCCAGACAGACUUCAUCAUUGUGCUAGCUGAUGGACAGGUGUCUGAGAUGGGCCCGUACCCAGCCCUGCUGCAGCGCAACGGCUCCUUUGCCAACUUUCUCUGCAACUAUGCCCCCGAUGAGGACCAAGGGCACCUGGAGGACAGCUGGACCGCGUUGGAAGGUGCAGAGGAUAAGGAGGCACUGCUGAUUGAAGACACACUCAGCAACCACACGGAUCUGACAGACAAUGAUCCAGUCACCUAUGUGGUCCAGAAGCAGUUUAUGAGACAGCUGAGUGCCCUGUCCUCAGAUGGGGAGGGACAGGGUCGGCCUGUACCCCGGAGGCACCUGGGUCCAUCAGAGAAGGUGCAGGUGACAGAGGCGAAGGCAGAUGGGGCACUGACCCAGGAGGAGAAAGCAGCCAUUGGCACUGUGGAGCUCAGUGUGUUCUGGGAUUAUGCCAAGGCCGUGGGGCUCUGUACCACGCUGGCCAUCUGUCUCCUGUAUGUGGGUCAAAGUGCGGCUGCCAUUGGAGCCAAUGUGUGGCUCAGUGCCUGGACAAAUGAUGCCAUGGCAGACAGUAGACAGAACAACACUUCCCUGAGGCUGGGCGUCUAUGCUGCUUUAGGAAUUCUGCAAGGGUUCUUGGUGAUGCUGGCAGCCAUGGCCAUGGCAGCGGGUGGCAUCCAGGCUGCCCGUGUGUUGCACCAGGCACUGCUGCACAACAAGAUACGCUCGCCACAGUCCUUCUUUGACACCACACCAUCAGGCCGCAUCCUGAACUGCUUCUCCAAGGACAUCUAUGUCGUUGAUGAGGUUCUGGCCCCUGUCAUCCUCAUGCUGCUCAAUUCCUUCUUCAACGCCAUCUCCACUCUUGUGGUCAUCAUGGCCAGCACGCCGCUCUUCACUGUGGUCAUCCUGCCCCUGGCUGUGCUCUACACCUUAGUGCAGCGCUUCUAUGCAGCCACAUCACGGCAACUGAAGCGGCUGGAAUCAGUCAGCCGCUCACCUAUCUACUCCCACUUUUCGGAGACAGUGACUGGUGCCAGUGUCAUCCGGGCCUACAACCGCAGCCGGGAUUUUGAGAUCAUCAGUGAUACUAAGGUGGAUGCCAACCAGAGAAGCUGCUACCCCUACAUCAUCUCCAACCGGUGGCUGAGCAUCGGAGUGGAGUUCGUGGGGAACUGCGUGGUGCUCUUUGCUGCACUAUUUGCCGUCAUCGGGAGGAGCAGCCUGAACCCGGGGCUGGUGGGCCUUUCUGUGUCCUACUCCUUGCAGGUGACAUUUGCUCUGAACUGGAUGAUACGAAUGAUGUCAGAUUUGGAAUCUAACAUCGUGGCUGUGGAGAGGGUCAAGGAGUACUCCAAGACAGAGACAGAGGCGCCCUGGGUGGUGGAAGGCAGCCGCCCUCCCGAAGGUUGGCCCCCACGUGGGGAGGUGGAGUUCCGGAAUUAUUCUGUGCGCUACCGGCCGGGCCUAGACCUGGUGCUGAGAGACCUGAGUCUGCAUGUGCACGGUGGCGAGAAGGUGGGGAUCGUGGGCCGCACUGGGGCUGGCAAGUCUUCCAUGACCCUUUGCCUGUUCCGCAUCCUGGAGGCGGCAAAGGGUGAAAUCCGCAUUGAUGGCCUCAAUGUGGCAGACAUCGGCCUCCAUGACCUGCGCUCUCAGCUGACCAUCAUCCCGCAGGACCCCAUCCUGUUCUCGGGGACCCUGCGCAUGAACCUGGACCCCUUCGGCAGCUACUCAGAGGAGGACAUUUGGUGGGCUUUGGAGCUGUCCCACCUGCACACGUUUGUGAGCUCCCAGCCGGCAGGCCUGGACUUCCAGUGCUCAGAGGGCGGGGAGAAUCUCAGCGUGGGCCAGAGGCAGCUCGUGUGCCUGGCCCGAGCCCUGCUCCGCAAGAGCCGCAUCCUGGUUUUAGACGAGGCCACAGCUGCCAUCGACCUGGAGACUGACAACCUCAUCCAGGCUACCAUCCGCACCCAGUUUGAUACCUGCACUGUCCUGACCAUCGCACACCGGCUUAACACUAUCAUGGACUACACCAGGGUCCUGGUCCUGGACAAAGGAGUAGUAGCUGAAUUUGAUUCUCCAGCCAACCUCAUUGCAGCUAGAGGCAUCUUCUACGGGAUGGCCAGAGAUGCUGGACUUGCCUAAAAUAUAUUCCUGAGAUUUCCUCCUGGCCUUUCCUGGUUUUCAUCAGGAAGGAAAUGACACCAAAUAUGUCCGCAGAAUGGACUUGAUAGCAAACACUGGGGGCACCUUAAGAUUUUGCACCUGUAAAGUGCCUUACAGGGUAACUGUGCUGAAUGCUUUAGAUGAGGAAAUGAUCCCCAAGUGGUGAAUGACACGCCUAAGGUCACAGCUAGUUUGAGCCAGUUAGACUAGUCCCCGGUCUCCCGAUUCCCAACUGAGUGUUAUUUGCACACUGCACUGUUUUCAAAUAACGAUUUUAUGAAAUGACCUCUGUCCUCCCUCUGAUUUUUCAUAUUUUCUAAAGUUUCGUUUCUGUUUUUUAAUAAAAAGCUUUUUCCUCCUGGAACAGAAGACAGCUGCUGGGUCAGGCCACCCCUAGGAACUCAGUCCUGUACUCUGGGGUGCUGCCUGAAUCCAUUAAAAAUGGGAGUACUGAUGAAAUAAAACUACAUGGUCAACAGUAUAUACACAGUAGUCUUUUUGCACUUGUUCACAAGGUUUGGGGAUUAGGAUCUUUGGAGGAGGCCAAGAGGAAGACUUUCUACACAUGUACAUGGUUGUAGUUACCUGAACUUCAGACCCAAGAGCUCUUGGCUGCAAAUAUUGCCUUCACAGCCAAAAUUCCCUGGGUAAUUGCCAGUAGCUCCUGCUCUGCUGUGCAGAUAUUGUAAAACGGUGAGAAAGGCCCUGAAAUCUGACCUGGGGCCUCUUGGGAAAGCUGCUGUGAACACCUCCACGUUAAUGUCAUCCCUCAGCCCUCUAUGCCUGUUUCUCUAGGGACUGAGAAGUGCAUGAUGCUUUUACUUCCUUGCUCAUUUCGAAGUCUGUUCCAGACAGUUCCUAUAACCAGUGAGGCCUCCAAGUCAUUCAUUUUCCUCAGUCUAGCCAAAGCUGAAUGUGUGAGCACAAAGAAGCCGAGAGGCCACCUCCUGCCCAGAGAGAAGCCACCCACACUCCCAGGUUGGCAGACAAGAUGUGAGGGGUGAAUUAAAUUUGUUUUCUUGAGCAAGCCAA